CUCCUUGCUGCUGCUGCCGCCGCCAAUCCUGGUCCGGUUGCCCGAGUUCCCGGAGGUCUCUCGCGGGACCUCUCUCACCGCCACCGCUCCUACUCUCGGGCUUCCAAAUCUGGGGCGAUGUCUCCCCAGGUUAAAUUACCCUAGCUCCUGCUCCAGAUCGCUUCCCCGUGCCCCGCCAGAGCCCAGUAGUUCAAAAAUUAAAUUUGGGGCAAGGGGUGCGCGCCAGAGCGCAGCUGUUUCUGGAGCCUGCGGCAGCGGUGGCGAGCCACAGGGCGGCGACCGUGAGCUCCGGGAGCUGCGCAAACCACCUGGAGACCAUGUCUGGGGAUGCGACCAGGACCCUGGGGAAAGGAAGCCAGCCCCCAGGGCCAGUCCCGGAGGGGCUGAUCCGCAUCUACAGCAUGAGGUUCUGCCCCUAUUCUCACAGGACCCGCCUCGUCCUCAAGGCCAAAGACAUCAGACAUGAAGUGGUCAACAUUAACCUGAGAAACAAGCCUGAAUGGUACUAUACAAAGCACCCUUUUGGCCACAUUCCUGUCCUGGAGACCAGCCAAUGUCAACUGAUCUAUGAAUCUGUUAUUGCUUGUGAGUACCUGGAUGAUGCUUAUCCAGGAAGGAAGCUGUUUCCAUAUGACCCUUAUGAACGAGCUCGCCAAAAGAUGUUAUUGGAGCUAUUUUGUAAGGUCCCACAUUUGACCAAGGAGUGCCUGGUAGCGUUGAGAUGUGGGAGAGAAUGCACUAAUCUGAAGGCAGCCCUGCGUCAGGAAUUCAGCAACCUGGAAGAGAUUCUUGAGUAUCAGAACACCACCUUCUUUGGUGGAACCUGUAUAUCCAUGAUUGAUUACCUCCUCUGGCCCUGGUUUGAGCGGCUGGAUGUGUAUGGGAUACUGGACUGUGUGAGCCACACGCCAGCCCUGCGGCUCUGGAUAUCAGCCAUGAAGUGGGACCCCACAGUCUGUGCUCUUCUCAUGGAUAAGAGCAUUUUCCAGGGCUUCUUGAAUCUCUAUUUUCAGAACAACCCUAAUGCCUUUGACUUUGGGCUGUGCUGAGUCUCACUGUCCACCCCUUCGCUGUCCAGAAUUCCCCAGCUUGUUGGGAGUCUACGUCACGGCUUGUCUUGGGAACCAAUCCGUCUCUCUUUCUUUUCUUUGAAGUUCCCAAUAAAAUGAAAACAGGAAAUGUAUUCUUCUGAUAAUCAUUUGUCUGACUCCUCUAGCCUGUAGCUGCUGCUACUGCUGCUUUUUUUUCCUUUUUUUUUUUGAGGCAAGAUCUUGCUUCGUUACUCAGGCUGGAGUGCAGUGGGACAGUCGGCUCACUGCAGCCUUGAACUCCUGGGCUCAGUUGAUUCUCCCGCCUCAGCCUCCUGAGAAGCUAGGACUACAGGUAUGUGUCACCACGCCCAGCUAAUUUUUAAAAAAAUGUUGUUGAGACAGGGUCUCACUAUGUUGCUCAGGCUGGUCUCCAUCUCCUGGCCGCAAGCCAUCCACCCAACUUGGUCUCCAAAGUGUUGAGAUUACAGGCAUGAGCCACCUGGCCUGCCUAGCCUGUAGCUUCUAACUAUUUUCUAGAAAGUGCCUGGUGCUAAUGUCAGAGCACAUUUUGGGAGCCUGUGUGCCUCCUAACUCCUUGGCCUUCAGCCUAGUUUGAUCUCCAGAUUAUUGGUGCAGAUGCUGAUGCUGAGGUUCAGGGUCAACCUAUGACUGAUGCUUGUCACUACAGAAUGGCACCCUCCAAAGACCUCCCUGGUGAAAGCUUAAGAAGAGGGAGAAGGAAGAAGAAAACACUCCAAACCUAAAUACCUUCCAUUUGGCAAAUGAAUGUCGCUGUCCACGUGGGCGAGUAUGAGUGUAAUUCUCCAAACUUUGGCCAUGGGCCUGGAGACACCGAGGGUCUUGUGACUGGAAAGAAUUCCAAAGCAGGAAAUGAAACACCGGUUUAUCACCCAGGACUAACUACGUCAGAAUUUCACUGGUGCUGUCAGGGCUCAGGAUGUCUCACAAAAUGUUCUAUAGCCGGCAUCCUGCCUUAAAAAAAUACACACGCCCCAAACCCAGCCACAAGCAAAGGUCAUUCCGUUGGAUUUGCGUCACACUCUCUUCCAAUUCAUCUCAACAAAUGCCUCUGGUUGCCUGUUGUGUACCAAGCCCAGGGGCACACUGGGGAUAAAGUUGAAAAAGACAUUGGCUCUGUCCCUGGGAGCCCCCAUCUCUCCACUUAUCUUGGUUGAGGUUUUAAACCUAGCGCUUUGGAGCUGCUUGUCUGUUGUAGGGAUGCUUGUCUCUGAUGUGGCCCCUCUGCCAGCUUCGCCAGGCAGUACCACCCCACUGAAGACAGCAAAGAGCUGAGGAUGGCUGGUGCCAACAGGUCCCUUGGGCUGGGAGCAUCUACUGCCUGCACUAUGGGAGGGGGACCAAGUUUGUCCAAUGCUGUUUCAUCUCAGUGUCUGAGGAUCAGCCUGUGAUCAUUUCAGCUUUGCUCAUGCUGGAUCCUUUCCCAUCCUCCUAGCUGUGCUGAGACACCAGGCAGCAACAGGAGCGAUGUUUUGCCUUGUCUGUGCUCCCUAAGGAGCUGUCUGCCACCUCUGCCUCUGAGACAGCCCAAAUCAGCCCUCCUCUCUCCCCACGUCUCAGUCUGGCCCUGCCAUCUGCUGGCUCUGGGUAUAUUUUGACCCAUGUAAAUAGUUACCAGGUGUUACUCUGUGCCAGCUGGACAGAAACAAGCCUGCUUGGUGAGGUGGCCAGAACUUCCAGAAGAGGCAGCGCAUGACAGGGGCAGUCUGCCGCACCAUCUGCUCCGGAUGUGGAGCCCUGUUGCCAUGGCACCCUAGUUAAUGCUGAGUGAGGUCUGUGAAUCACCGUUUUCCUGGGAUCUUUGCUCCAAGAAGAGGGGAAUCUUCUCCUGUGGCCUCUCAUAGGACUUAGGAGAUUGAUCAGCCUUUUGCCGGUACAAAUCCUGCAUGCUAGUGAGUGCUUGUCAUAAGACCAAAGUUACCACUGAUGCAACAGGAAAUGGCAUGCCUCUGGCUCACCAAAAUGAAGGUGUUCUCUUUUGGGGCUCCGCACACUAAUUUAGAAAGCUUGAAGAACCAGGAAUUAUAGAAUGGAGAAAAGCACUCAUGGGGGAGGUUUGCAGCCUGGUGGCCUAUAGCCCAGUUUGGGAUUUGAGUGCCUCUUGGCCAGGCAUGCUCCCUGCUGUUUACCAGGGUCCUGGUCACCUGCACAUCCUUACACUUCCUCCAUCUCGCUUCUUUGUCACUUGUCUGACCCACAGAGAAAACUGAGUUAUCAAUCUUUGAAUAAAACUAGAAGGAUGUGGCCUGGAGAAAAGAGGGAAGGAGGUAAUUAAAUAAUGCUCCAUGAAGAACUUUAAAAAUAUGCUUCUUAAUUAAUACAUGUGGAAAGAAUACAUAUGGGUUAAAAAUACAAUAAUGUAAAAGAAUAGAAAAUCUUCCAUUAUCUUGUGUCCUAGAGAUAACCACUUUUAGUAAUUGGUGUCUACCUUUUUUUCCCCUUUUCUUUUAAAUAAUAGAGAUGGGGUUUCGCUAUGUUGACCAGGCUGGUCUUGAACUCCUGGCUUCAAGUGAUCCUCCCAUCUCGGCAUCCCAAAGUGCUGGGAUUAUAGGUCUGAGUCAUCAUGCCUGGUGGGUGUCUAUCUUAUAAAAAGCACUAAACUUAAAGAUUUAAAGGUGAGAGCCUGUAUUAGGCCAUUCUCAUGGUGCUAUAAAGAACUGCCCAAGACUGAGUAAUUUAUAAAGGAAAGAGGUUUAAUUGACUCACAAUUCCACAUGGCUGGGGAAGCCUCAGGAAACUUUCAAUCAUGGUGGAAGGGGAAGCAAACAUGUCCUUCUGCACAAGGUGGCAGAAGAGAGAAGUACAGAGCCAAAGAGGGAAAAACUCCUUAUAAAACCAUUAGAUCUCAUGAGAACUCACUCACUGUCAUGAGAAAAGCAUAGGGAAAACACUCCCACAAUCGAAUCACCUCCCUUGAGGUCCCUCCCCCAACAUGUGGGGAUUAUAAUUCAGAUUAAAAUUGAAGAUGAGAUUUUAGGUGGAGCACAGCCAAACCAUAUCAGAGCCAUUCUCUAUCUUUUGCAGAUUGGAAAAAUAAAAAAAUUAGUUUAAACCACAGCAUUUAAAAGAAAUGGUCAUAGAUGAUGUUAACAUCAGAAUGGAGGUUGUGUGGAGUUCCCCUCCUUGGAGGUUCUGAGCUACAGCCUAGCCUGGACUCAGUCCAGUUACAAUCUAACAUGGCUAGGGGGAGGAGGGAGCAUGAUGGGGCAGGGCUUGUGUGGCUGGGACAGCUGGCUAUGGUCGUGGUGCUGGUGACUAAAUGGUACUUGAAAUUUCUUUUAGAUCUAAAAUUCUGUGAUAUGGUUUGGAUCUGAGACCCCACCAAAUUUCGUGUUGAAAUGUAAUCCCCAAUGCUGGUGGGAGGUGAUUGGAUCAUGGGGGUAGAUUUCUCAUGAAUGGUUUAGCACCAUUCUCUUGGUGCUGUUCUCAUGAUAGUGAGUGAGUUCUCAUGAGUUCUGGUUGUUUAAAAGUGUGCAGCAUCUCCCUGACCCCUCUUGCGCCAGCUCCCACCAUGGGAGAUGCCUCGCUCCCCCUUUGCUUUUUGCCAUGAGAGGAAGCUUCCUGAGGGCUCUCCAGAAGCAGAAUCUACUACACUUCUCAUACAGCCUGCAGAACCAUGAGCCAAUUAAACCUCUUUUUAAAAACACUUUUAUUUUAAGUUCAGGGGUACAUGUGCAGGAUGUGCAGGUUCGUUCCAUAGGUAAACAUGCGUCAUGGGGUUUGUUAUGCAGAUUAUUUCAUCACCUAGAUAUUAAGUCUAGUAUCCAUUAGUUAUUUUUCCUGAUCCUCUCCCUCCUCCCACCCUGCACCCUCUGAUAGGCCUCAGUGUGUAUUGUUACCCUCCACAUGUCCAUGUGUUCUCAUGAUUUAGCUCCCACUUAUAAGUGAGAACAUGCAGUUUUUGUAAACCUGUUUUCUUUAGGGAAAGUUUAGAAUUUUCUAGAGACUGGUUGUAUGGUUGUGACCAAAAUGCCAGUAGUGAUAUGGACAGUGAAGGCCAGGCUGAGGAGGUGAUGGAAAUGAGGAACUUACUGGGAACUGGAGCAAAGGUCACUUUUGUUAUGCUUUAGCAAAGAACUUGGCUGCAUUGUGCUCCUGGCCUAGGGACCUGUGGAAGUUUGAACUUGAGAGUGAUGAUUUUAGGGUAUCUGGCAGAAAAAAUUUCUAAGCAGCAAAGCAUUCAAGAUGCGCCCUGGCUGCUUUCAACAACCUAUGCUCAUAUUUGUGAGCAAAGAAAUUAUGUUAAGUUGGAACUUAUAUUUACAGGGGAAGCAGAGCGUAAAAGUUUGGAGAAUUUGCAGCCAGCUAUGUGGUAGAAAAGAAGAGCCCGUUUUCAGGGAAGGAAUUCAAGCAGGCUGCAGAAAUUUGCAUAAGUAAAAAGGAGCCAAGUGCUAAUGGCCAAGAAAAUGGGGAAAAGGCCUUGAAGGCAUUUCAGAGACCUUUGUGGCAGCCCCUCCCAUCACAGACUCAGAGGCCUAGGAGGACAGAAUGACUCUGAGUAUUAAAGUAGAUUUAAUCUAAAUCAUAAAGUACAAGCUAGAGCAAUCCCUCCAGUGCUGCAGAAACUGCCUGCAUGUGGCUCCCACAUUGUUUCUUGGAGCUUUGGUGGUGGUAGGGGUGGCAGGGGCAGGUGUUAUGUUUCUUGGUUUCUCACCUUCAGGUCUCCUUACCCAUGUUUCCUUUGUCAGAGUCAUUGGCCUUGAUGGAGGGGAGACUGGGUUACUCUGAGUUGAGAAGCAAGCUUGACUGCCCUGUGGUUUAUAUCAGCCUAGCUUAGUUUGUUUUCUGAAGUCUUCACAAAUAACCAAAUAUCCAGCCCAGUGCAGUUCUCAAUGAGUAGUCUCCAGUUCCCAUCCCCCACCACACACACACACCAAACACUGUGCCCACCUGGGAGACCCAUUUUCAUUUAUCUUCUUCUUUGAGUGCCUGGAAGGCUGAACAUUUGAUCUUUUCAAACAUUUUUCUCUCAUCUGGCCUGUUAGCGCUCUUGAGCCUUUGAAAAUGCCAUUUCCUCUACAUACUAUUCUUCCUCAGAGCAGCCCUCUGUUUUUUUUUCCAACCAGUCUUUUCUCUUGCAAAGUUCAGAUCAAAAUUCUUCUUUAUGUAAAGAGAAGUGGCGUGCCAUAGGGGUUACAAACAGGGCUUCAAGGUUAGCACUGGGAUCAAAUUCCGACUUUGCAACUUAACUUUCUUGAGUAAGUUGCUACACCUCUAUUAGCCUCAGUUUCUUAUCUGUAAAAUGGGACGGCUAAGUACCUAUUUCAUUGGGCUGUUGAAUAAUGAUGGUCUCAUCUAUGCAAGGGCUUAGUACCAGCUGGGUGAAACUCAGUGAAUGGCAGGCAACCCUAUUAUGACUAGGCUUCUGCCAAUGAUCAGACUUGAACCCUGUGCUCAUCCCCCCAUCACUUUGUGGAACUAGAUGUCCUACGUUGCACAUGGCUUGAUUCAUGGUUUGGAGUUGUUUUCUGGUUGUUUCCUGUGUGCAGGUUUAAUCUCAACCUGUGAUCCCUUGAAAGCUGCAAUUUUAUCCCUCCCCGUCCUCCUCCCUCUCACCCCAAGGCCAAGUUUAAUACUGUGCAUUCUGAAAUCUUGCAAUGUUGAUGAUGUAAAAUAAAUCUUCUCUCCUGUGUUUCUGAAGAAUA